GUUUUAUUGACAAUACAUGCAUCAUAUCUUUUGACUUUGAAGGAUAUCUCAUGUCAAAGGAAUCAAGUUAUGAUUUAUAGAGGAUUCAGCUGGAAUACCUUGUGGGUGCUGGCUGAGGGUGGCAAAACGCCUACCGAGACAUGAAGGUUUUAGCCACUAGUUUUGUCCUUGGGAGCCUGGGGUUGGCCUUCUACCUGCCUUUGGUGGUGACUACACCUAAAACACUGGCCAUCCCUGAGAAGCUGCAAGAAGCUGUGGGGAAAGUUAUCAUCAAUGCCACAACCUGUACUGUCACCUGUGGCCUUGGCUAUAAGGAGGAGACCGUCUGUGAGGUGGGCCCUGAUGGAGUGAGAAGGAAAUGUCAGACUCGGCGCUUAGAAUGUCUGACCAACUGGAUCUGUGGGAUGCUCCAUUUCACCAUUCUCAUUGGCAAGGAAUUUGAGCUUAGCUGUCUGAGUUCAGACAUCUUGGAGUUUGGACAGGAAGCUUUCCGGUUCACCUGGAGACUUGCUCGAGGUGUCAUCUCCACUGACGAUGAGGUCUUCAAACCCUUUCAAGCCAACUCCCACUUUGUGAAGUUUAAAUAUGCUCAGGAGUAUGACUCUGGGACAUAUCGCUGUGAUGUGCAGCUGGUAAAAAACUUGAGACUCGUCAAGAGGCUCUAUUUUGGGUUGAGGGUCCUUCCUCCUAACUUGGUGAAUCUGAAUUUCCAUCAGUCACUUACUGAGGAUCAGAAGUUAAUAGAUGAGGGAUUGGAAGUUAAUCUGGACAGCUACUCCAAGCCUCACCACCCAAAGUGGAAAAAGAAGGUGGCGUCAGCCUUGGGAAUAGGAAUUGCCAUUGGAGUGGUUGGUGGCGUGUUGGUGAGGAUUGUCCUCUGUGCGCUAAGGGGGGGCCUGCAGCAGUGACAGCUUCAAGAACUUAACAGCCUUGCUCCUGAAGAACUGGCUGCCCAGGAAGCCAAGCUAGCUUUUUAGGGGAGUGUUCCAGCUGCUGGUAGUGGAUCAGCUUAGAGGGAACACUCCCACAGCCAAAAGAAUGAGUGGGAGAAAUGGAGGGGACAAUCUCCUGGGAGCUAUGCGCAGUAACCUAACUUCCUUAUGUCCCAUGGAUCUCUUCCUGAUCUUCCCUGCCCAUUGGGUACCCAGGAAACUGCAAGCAUUGCCUGUGUUCCUGGGAAGAGUUCUAAGAAGCUUGCAUUCAUUUUCUACCCUUUAUGACUUGGAUGCCUCCCCACCUCCAUUUCCCCUCUUCUGAGCUGUGUAUUCAUGUAGAGGGAUGUAUUCAGCCUUUUUAGUGAACAUUUUUUUUCAAUAAAAGUAAUUCACAGUA